GCCCCCCACACAUUUCCAGCUCGCACCCGGGCUCCGACCGCUCGCCCCGCUCCUCUCGCUGUGCUCCCGGCCGGUGCCGCGGGUUCGGUCCGGGCGCCGGUGCGCUCCUGCCGGUCCUCGUGCCCGGGACUCCGGGUCCCCGCGGGCUGCUGCGCACGAUGAAGCUGGCCCUGCUCCUGCCCUGGGCGUGUUGCUGCCUCUGCGGGUCGGCGCUGGCCACCGGCUUCCUCUAUCCCUUCUCGGCCGCAGCUCUGCAGCAGCACGGCUACCCCGAGCCCGGCGCCGGCUCCCCUGGCAGCGGCUACGCGAGCCGCCGGCACUGGUGCCAUCACACAGUGACACGGACGGUGUCCUGCCAGGUGCAGAAUGGCUCGGAGACGGUGGUCCAGCGCGUGUACCAGAGCUGCCGGUGGCCGGGGCCCUGCGCCAACCUCGUAAGUUACAGGACUCUGAUCAGACCCACCUACAGAGUGUCCUACCGCACGGUGACGGUGCUGGAGUGGAGAUGCUGCCCUGGCUUCACCGGGAGCAACUGUGAUGAGGAAUGCAUGAACUGCACCCGGCUCAGUGACAUGAGUGAGCGACUGACCACACUGGAGGCCAAGGUCCUCCUGCUAGAAGCAGCAGAACGGCCCUCCAGCCCGGACAACGACCUGCCAGCCCCCGAGAGCACUCCGCCGACCUGGAAUGAGGACUUCCUCCCCGACGCCAUCCCUCUUGCUCACCCUGUGCCACGACAGAGAAGGCCCACGGGCCCAGCCGGGCCCCCGGGGCAGACAGGACCACCAGGGCCUGCAGGCCCCCCCGGGUCUAAAGGUGACCGAGGCCAGACAGGAGAGAAGGGUCCAGCGGGGCCGCCUGGGCUCCUGGGGCCUCCAGGGCCCCGUGGGCUUCCUGGAGAGAUGGGGCGCCCCGGCCCCCCAGGACCACCCGGCCCAGCAGGCAACCCAGGCCCCUCACCAAACAGCCCCCAGGGCGCCCUCUACUCCCUGCAGCCGCCUACAGACAAAGACAAUGGAGACUCAAGGCUGGCCUCUGCCAUCGUGGACACAGUGCUGGCAGGUGUCCCAGGACCCCGGGGUCCCCCUGGUCCACCAGGUCCCCCUGGGCCUCGAGGUCCCCCAGGACCCCCAGGAACACCUGGAUCCCAGGGCCUGGCUGGAGAGCGAGGCACAGUGGGGCCGUCCGGUGAACCUGGCGUGAAGGGGGAAGAAGGAGAGAAAGCCGCCACUGCAGAGGGCGAGGGGGUGCAGCAGCUGAGAGAGGCCCUGAAGAUCCUGGCAGAGCGAGUCCUCAUCCUGGAGCACAUGAUUGGGAUCCACGAUCCCCUGGCCUCCCCAGAGGGAGGUUCUGGCCAGGAUGCUGCCCUGAGAGCCAACCUCAAGAUGAAGAGGGGUGGCGCCCAACCCGAUGGGGUCCUUGCUGCCCUGCUUGGGCCCGACCCUGGACAGAAGAGCGUGGACCAGGCCAGCAGCAGGAAGUGAGAGCCCACUGCUCCAGGACACCCUGUCCUGGCUAGAGACCCAGCCCCAGAGGCCUGAGCCGCCGCUGUUUCCUAAAGAUGCCCCCAGGGGAACUGGGCUCCAGGCAUGGAUGAUUGUGAGGACAUGGGGGGCUUUGGGGACAGAUAAUGUCUCCAGGGGCAGGGUCUGGAGGGGCCAACACCCUCAUCAGAGCCCUCCUCUGGCCUGUCCCCUCCCCUACCCCCACUCCCGGCUGGAGACGGGGUCUGGGUGGGCUGGGUGCUGGGAAUGAGAAUAAUCCUAAUACCCAUCAUUUAUUGAGUCCCUGCUGUAACUGGCCCUGUCCAGGGAACUUUCGUUACGUUGUCUCAUUAUUUAACCCUUAGGAGGUAAGCUUAUUAUCCCCACUUCACAAGGGGACCGAGGCUCAGACGGUAGAAAUAACCCUCUCUUGGCCACCAGAUCACGGGUGGCAGGGGCAGGAUUUGAACCCAGGACCCUCAGUUCCUGAAGCCAUGUUCUCUCGACCCUGCCAGCUUCCCCUCUUCGAGAGAAAACUCAGACAGGGAGGGCGCAGGGCCAGAACGGCUCCUUAAGGCAGGCAGGGCUGCGGGGAGGCUGGGCCAGCCAGCCUGAGGGGGUAGGCAGGGUCCUGCAGGGCCUGGGGCUUCCCUUCCUCAUCCCCCUUCCCCACUGGCUGGGGGAGCAGCCUGGACUGCAGCUCUCAGAGGCCAGGGAGACCCUGAAUAAAUCACUGCCAGCCAUACGGACUUGAGGACCUUGAGAGAGAAGCAUUGGGGGUGCAAGUGUCCACCAAACCAGAUAGGCAUCCCUGGCCACUGCCUCCCAGUCUUGCUGAGCCCACCCGCUCUCUCUGGGUCCAUCCCAUCCCUGAGCCAGGGGAGGCAGCAUUUCAUGGGCAUGUCUAUCAGAGGUGGGACUUGCAGCCUCUGCCCCACGAGUUUGUCUCUCAGUGGACUCUAUAGGUUUGCUACUUUUGCAUGACACAGCAAGCCCAGUGUCCCCUUUGCAAGCUGCAGAGAGGGAAACAGAGUCCCAGGCCUGCUGGGAAGAGAUGCUCCUGCCUCCCACCUUCCAGAGUUGGGGGCCUGGCAGGCUCCAUGGCAGGCACCAGGUCCCUAGCAGCCCAGAACAGCUCUGACUGGAGCCCUCAAGGCCUCUGGGGCCAGGGUCUCCGUGAUCAGCUCAGCCCUGGUGUUCCUCUCUUGCUGGGCUGGGACCUGGGACACAGCCACGGCAGCAAACUCAGAGAAUUGAAGGUGCUGGCGCCACCCUGGGGCACUCUGUCUUCACAGCAGGAGUGACUGUCUCCAGUGCUCUUGGUACUCCUGUUUGGCUGUGGCCUGGUCCCUCUGGGCCCUGGGAUCUUCUUCUGGCCCUUGAGGCAGGUCUGGAGAGGCAGUCUCUGUCUUCAUGGAGGGGUGGUCAGAGGCGGGCGGGACCACCAGCCUGUAGCGUUAUUAUUAUAUGUGACAAUAAAGGUGCUCUCCCCAC